AAAAAAAAGAAGUUAUUUAGAGCACAAAUACAAAAAGUCACUUAAUAGUUGAUGUUAUUUUUAAAUUUUGUUAGUUUCUCUGAAAGAAUAUGCCUAUUUUGCUGAAACUUGUGACCACUUUAUUCUUCAUUUUCCUUUUGUAGGAGUUAUUACAACAGCAACAUUGACCCAUGAUUGUGUCUUUAUGAAAAUUGGGGUAUUUUAUUUAUUUAUUUAUUUAGGCAUGAAAGUCCUUAAAAUGUAUAACACUGAAGAAAAUCAACAUAAGUCCAUGCAUUUUAUAGGUUGAUCAGUGAAAGGAAGGCCAAGAUAGCUAGGUUUUUAGUAACACUGGUUAAGAGCCCAUAACACAGAAGGUGUAAAUUGGGUCACUUAACUGUUAACAGCAUUGCAGUGACUUCACAAUCUGAUACUCAAAAGUAGUAUUGGUUAAAAUAAUAGAAGUGUUAAAGAGUUAUUUUCUAUCUAUGUUUCAUUUGCCUUUUAAUCCCAUUUUCUUGUUACAACAGAUAUGCAUACAUGUUUUAUGUAUUACAAAUGAAGUACUUAUAUAUUUUAAGGUCAGCAAAAACAUGCUAGGUUCAGAUGUGUUUCUGCAUACGCUUGGAAACAGUAACUGUGAUUUCAUCCAUUACUAUUUCAAACAAGUUUAAUGACUGGAUGUAAUUCCUACAGGUAUAGAUUUUUAAAGUGCAGCUUACACUUUAAGAACUCAUUGGAGAAAUUUGCGUGGAUUUUCAUUCUACUCUGAUUUAAAGGUUUUAGGCAAAUUUGAAAAAUUUCAAAAUUGCUUCAUUUUUCAGUGAAAAUUUGUUUAUACAAAGAGUAAUAUAGGGCUUUUUUUGCUGUAGAAUUUUAUCAAUUACUCAUCCCAUAUUGUUUAGUACUUAGUAUCUUAUGCAUAUUAAGUAAUUUUAUCAAUUACUCAUCACAUAUAAUUUAGUACUUAAUAUCUUAUGCAUAUUAUUAAUAUCUUAUGCAUAUUAAGUACUAAAUAAUAUGGGAUGAGUAAUUGAUAAAAUUGUGCAGGGUUGGGAAACUCUUGCUUCCUGGAAGUUUAUGGCUCUGAAGACUUACCCUCACAUUCAGUUUCCACAUUAUUCAGUCUCGGUUCUACAUUUCACCCAUAAAAUUUUCUGGAAAAAUAUCCACUCAUAUCAGUAAAAUAGUUGUCUACUUAUAUUCUUUUCAGAGGAAUUAUAAAUGCAGAAACCUCAUAAGCAAUGUGAUGUUGAAAACAGUGAAAUAACAGUAUUAUAGGGAAUAAAUCAUAGUAUGUUUGAGUACUAAAAAGAAAGAAAAUUGUUUCCAUGUGCUCUAAAGGAAUUUGAAUUUAGUUUCCAGAAUUUGGAUUUCAAUAAAGUACUUUUGAACCUUUUCCUAUUAUUAUAAUCUUAGUAACAUUAUCCUCAUCAGGUUUGAUUUGAUUUUAAUAGCAAAAUACAUUUCUAUAUGCUUAUCAAAUAAUUCUACUGUUAAAAUACUGCUAUGUAUACAAUAUUAAACAUAUCAUUACCAUAGUUGAUACAUGAUAGAAUUAGUCCGGUCUUCAGAUCUUCAUUAAAUAAUGUUAUUAAAAUUCCCUGCAUUCCAUGGGGGAACCACAGUGUGUCUGGUGUAAAACCUUUUGGAUAGUCUUUGUGUCUAGUUUGAAUUGCUUUUGUUCAUAAAAUUCUGCCAUGUAGAGUUAUUUCUGAAUAUCUUAUCAGUUGAGAUAAACCACAAGUACCUGAAGCGAAAUGGAUGUCUGCGUAAUCUCAAGAAAUCUUCAGGUUCAGAAAUAUGCGUUCACUGAAGAGCAAAAUCAGUUAAUCUUUAAAAUAAAAUGUAACGAACCAAUAAAAGAACCACAGUUCAGAUGGCUGACAUCAUACUAAAUGUCUUCCAGAAAACAGAGAUUUUCUCAUAGUGUGUUUUUUGGAUGAAUUUUUCCCUUAUAGAAUAUACAAAGACUCAAUUGAUUGAGAACUCAAAGCAGUUGGUGGCUCUGAUAUGGGUUUAUUGCCUCUAUUAGAUUAGAAGUAAGACUAUAAAUGACAGAUGGUAUCUUCUAGCCUACUUUCUAAUUACAAAACAAGUAAUACAUAUAGGUUUUCCAUCUCAUUAAGCACAGAUACAAAUAAAAAUGACUUAUUUUUCAGAAAAUUAUAAUAGCAUAGAGAUAAAAAUGUACAACUAUUUUUAUUUUAACAUGGAUUUCUGUUUAGUAGGAUAACAAAAGAAGUUGAUUUUUCAGAAGUUAAAUUGGCACUUUGUAAUUUUAUAUUGUCAUAUAGAAGGUGAUCUCAAGAAUAAACUAAAAUUAUAGCUAUAACUUGGCCACCAGAAAGUAAUAGCUUUUUCCUUCAGGCAUUAGUCAACAAAGUCAUAGGAGGCUGCUUGUGCUAGGAUGUAUAAUUUCCUGUUAAGUUUAUGGAAAAUAAUAGACAGGAAUUAUUGAAAAUAAGGGCGUGGCUAUAGGAGAGGUUAAAACAAAAGUAACAGAACUCAUGCCCAGCUUUAUGUUUCUUUUGUGGGGGGUGACACAGAGAUUGGGAGUGUGGCAGGCAGGGUGGGAUUGAGGAGGGUGAGAACCAGAGGAAGAAGCAAGGAACAUAGGGUACAGACUAAGAGUAAAAACUGAUAAUUAAAAGAAUUAUUUGUUCUCAGUCUUUCUUUGUACCUUAAAAAAAAAACUCAUUCUCUGUGUGACUGUUGGUAGAAACUGCCUCAGAAUAACAGGUGCUGAGAAGCAAGAAACAGUCUGAAUCAGUGGAGAGUACACUGGACUAGAAACCUGGUCAUGUGUAAAGUCAGUGUCUUCCACAGCCUCAGUUUUAUCACCUGUAAAAUAAUGAGUUUAUAGAUCAUCUGCACAGUUCCUUCUAGUUUUAUUUUAUUGUGAUUUGGUAGUUUAAUAAAUCAAGCCUUCCAGACUGACUUACUUGCUUUUAUGCUUGCAGAAUUCCAAGUGAGGAUCAUAGACAACCUUCCCAGGGAAAGUUUGUACUAACUCAUUAAUAUAAAUUUAAAUGGGUUUGCUCUGACUCCUAGAAAUUUAAAGGUGGCUGAUCAGAUUCUCCCUAUAACUAGUUUGACAUCACUGAAACCUCUCAUUACACAUUUCAAGUCCAGAAAACAGAAGUUUUGUGAGCCAUCAAGAGCCUUGUGGAGGUAUUCUAACUAUGAACCUAUUUUGGCGCAAAUUUUAUAAAGGAGAAAGAAUUAUCACUUUAAUUCUAAAUGCAAAUCUAUUUUAGAUUUGAGUUCAGUAUAAUCUCAUUAGAUAAAAAACUCCCAUGAGAAUGGCAGCUGAAGAUUUGGUUACAGGGCUUACAUAUUCAGGGACAUGUGAUGUGUUCAAAGGGUGAAUUUUAUGUUUUUUGAAGUGAAGAGGAUAAAAAUUAGUGAUAUAUAAUAUUAGAUGCAAACCAUUAAGUGUUCAAAAGCAGUUCAUUGGGUAAGAAUAUUUACCCAACAUAUUCCUAAAGUUAGGAGACUCGUGGUUUCUGGCAUAAAAGCUGAGAGAGUACAUACUGUAGUAUUUGAACAAGGACAUGGCAGAGUGACAAAUUAUAUCAAAAUCUGAGAUGGGUGGAGGCACAUCUAAACAGAGGCUGGAUUGUCCUGGGUUUGGAUAGAGUUUAAAACUUUCAUGGGGCUUCUCUUUUUAAGCUGCCAUGGAGAGUAAGUGUAGUUCAAAAGCAAAAAAAAAAAAAAAAAAAAAAAAACCCCAAAAAACCAGCAAUUGAUUCUGCAGAAUUUUAGUAUUUAGUAACACUUUCCAUUAAUGGUACAUUAAUAAGUCAUGUCUCCUAAUGUACAAAGUAUUGUGAAGCUUCCAAAUUGUAUCUUGUCAAACAUAACAAACCAUAUUACAGGAUUCAUCUGAAAGGUGAGUGUUCAUUUUCGCCAUUACUGGCAACUGAGAAAUGAUUUUACUAUAUGACUUAUAGUACUGUCAGUAAUGUCUAUAAGUGAGCCAACUUCAGGAAAAACACAUAUCUCCAUUAAAAAGACAUGAAUAUAGAAUAGUGCAUAAAGGUGUAGGCUCUGGAGCCAGAUCGCCACAGCACAAACCUGGCUCCACUACUUACUAGCUAUGGGAAUACAGACAGAUUACAUAUGACUUGUAUAUACAGUCAGCCUCCAUUUCUGUGGGUUUAGUAUCCUUGGUUUCGACCAACUGUGAUCUGAAAAUACUCAGGGAGGAGAAAAGAAUGGUUGUGUCUAUACUGAACAUGUACAAACUUUUUCCUGUUGUUAUUGACUAAACUCAACAGUAUAACAACUACUUACAUAGCAUUUGCAUUGUAUUAGGUAUUAUAAGUAAUACCUAAUGUGUGUAGUUUAUAUGCAAAAUACUACACCAUUUAAUAUAAGGGACUCAAACGUGAUCCACAAAGGACUCCGUGGAUUAUGGUAUCCUCGGGAGGUUGUGGAACCAAUCCCUCACACUUACUGAGAAAUGAUUUUAACUAGAUAUCUGGCUUGUCAGCGCCUACCUGUAACCAAGGUGAAAUACUAGAGACACAUUGCAUUAUACAUUUCAAAGCUUCAGUGUUUCCACCUGCUAAAUUAUUAAUAGGUUAUUAAUCGUAUUUCUCUUACAGUUAUUUAGACUUAAAAGACUUAUCUAUAAAAGAGUUUAUAAAUAUGUCUAACACAUAGUGUUUAAAAAUAAUAGCUGUUAGAUUAUUAUGAUUAUUGUCUGUUUUGUAUUUCAAAUAUAUUAAUGGUUAGAUGGCCAAAGGAAUAAACAGGAUUUGCUUUAAAAUAUGGUCAAAACAAAAAUUAAAUAUUAACUAUAAAUUAAAUAUAAAAUACCCCCAGUAAAAUUAAUAGAAUUAUAAAAGUAACAAAUUGCAUAUCUGCCAUCUGAAAAGUUGCAUUUUGGCAUCUGAGAUAAAAUAUUAGCUCAUUGGUAAGAGAUUGAACUUUAGUGUCAGAUUUGUCUAUUUCUUAAGUUGUUAGGCAUCCCAAAGAUAGUAUUUGUUAGGCAAACUUGCAUUAAAAAUUAAGAAAAGAGAGAUUAAGUACUAAACUAAGAAAAAUAAUUAGGUUUUUAAAAAGAGUAAUGUAACCUGUUGCUCUAAGAAUUUCCUUUUUAAAAUUCCUAUUGCAUCUUUCAUUUAUUCAUUGUUCUACAACCAGCUUUGGUUGAAUAUUACAGGAAAUGUUUUAGUUAAGCAAAGUUUGUCUUUCUACAAUCUUCCACUGUGGUUUUUGAGACCCUUCCCUUAAUAUACCCUGCUUUUAUUGUGCCCAGUUGUAUUAAUUUUCUAGGGCUGUUGUAAUAAAGUAUCAUACAUAAACUGUGGCUUAAAACAAUAGAAAUUUAUUCUCUCUCAAUUCUUGAGACUCAGAAAUCAAGAUGUUGGCAGGGCCAUGCUCCCUCUGAAGCCUCUAGAGGAGGGCCCUUCCUUGCCUCUUACAGUUUAUGAUAGUACCGGGCAUUUCUUGGCUUGUGGCAGAAGAGCUCCAAUCUCUGCCUGUCUUCACAUGGCUGUCCUCCUUUUGUGUGUGUCUGAGUCUCUUUUCUUUUUAUAAGGAUGACAGCCAUACUGGAUUAGGACCUACUCUAAUCCAGGAUGACAUCAUAUUAAUUUGAUUAUAUCUACAAAGACCAUUUCCAAAUAAGGUCAUAUACACAGGUAUUGUGGGUUAGAACUUGAGCAUAUCUCUUUGAAGAAACACAAUUCAACCCAUAAGCAUUUUUACCAUGGCAGCCCACUGAGUUUCUUCUUUAACUGCCCCCCCUUCCUUCCUUCCGUCUUUCCUUCCUUCCGUCCUUCCUUCCUUCCUUCCUUCCUUCCUUUUUUUCCUUCCUUCCUUCCUAUCCAUCCAUUACAUAAAAUGAACAUCUGCUGUGUGCCCGACAUUUUCCUAGGCAGUAGGAACACCGGAUAGAGUGACACAAAGUUCCUGAUCUCAUGCACUUAUAUUCUAAGUCAAUAGACAAGUGACAUUUAACAUAUAGAACAUCUUUGAGAAUAAUUUUUACAAAGAUCAAUAAAACAAGGAAAGAGGAUCAAGAGAUAUGGGGGCAGAGGGGGAUGGCAUGUGGGUGAGAGGUACAUUUCAGACUGGAUGGUCAGUGCAAGCUAGCUGCCCUGCUACACAUACCUAUCUGAACCCAAUGUGCUGACUCACACAUGUAACGUAUUAAAAAGGUCUUUCUAUAAAUAAUUUAUUAAGUCAGAGGAGGGGUGCUAAUAUAGAUUUGAUUUUAGAAUGUAGAAAAGAUCGCUUUGAGGAGGGUCUCAUGCUGUAUUCAUCCUCCCAAUAUGUGCUAAGUGCUUACUGGGUGACGGGAGCUGUGUUAGGUCAGAGGAUGCAAUGGUGAGCAAGAAAAGGUGGCCUCUGCCCUCAUGGGACUUUCUCUGAAAUCCUGAUACAAUGUGGAAGGCAUUCUUAGGUAACAAAGAACUAGCAGCUGAUUGGUAUAUGGGGAGGAGUUAAUUCAGAUUUGACUUUACUUACAUCUUUCCUCCUGAUCUCAAGGCAAAAUAACAGAAUAUAGUCUAAUUAGUUGUUUUAAAGACAUAUUCUACAUACUUAUAUCUUACUGACUAAAGGUCAGUUAUCAAAAUUAUAGGGAGGUGAGAAAAGUUUUAGUGUAAGUGUUGAUGACUGACCUCCAAAUAAACUAUAUUGUUUUCUUUGGAUUUAAUAUGUUCUAGGAUUAUUUUUACAGAAAUAUUAUGGUGGAAAAUAUUGUUGUGAGCUACAUAGCCCAGAUGUGAGUCAUGAAAGCUGGUAUAAACCAGAUUUUAUUUGAUGAUUUGUUUAUUGACUUUUAGAAUAGAGAAUAAAAAGAAAUUGUGUACUUUCAUUUAAGAAAACAAAUCUUCAUUUUGUGAAGGACAAAUCAAAGUUUGCUAAGUAGCUCACCUAAAAAAUGACCUAACUUGUUACCCUGAUUUCCUGUAGACUGUGUGUAUCUGCCAGCUAUUGUUUUACUAGGAUGAGUGAAUCUCUGCCAAAGGAUUUAAAAGCUCUUCUAGAACUAGAAAAUUCCUUAGUGUACAGAAAUAAGAUUUGCUGAGAUAAAUGUUCAUCAAAAGGCAAUGCAUCAAGCUAAGGGAAAAAUCUCCAGACACACAGGAAGAUUGUACGUUUAGGCUUUCUUCUAUGUCAUGUUAAAAAUUAUGAAAUGAAUCUGCUGCUAGUCUGAGCACCAGACUAAACCAGAAUGAAACCUGUCAAGCUCUGUCUCGUUAGCGCUAUGCCAGCCAUGGUGAGAUCAAAGGGUAACCAUGGCUUUCACAGAGCACUUCCUCAGGUCCUUUUGGCAUCUUUUUGGCAUCUUUGACUCAGACUAACAUCACCAGUUCUGAUCUCUUCUGCUUUCUGGAAGCACAGGGUAGAUGGUUCCUGACUUCCCUUUUGUUGUAUGUUUCAUCUUGCAUUGAUACUUUUUUCUCCACUUGGCCCCUGUCCAACACGUAACUUGUUUUAGAUUAUAUAUAUGUAUAUAUAUUUAUAUAUCUCCAAAUGGGGAUGUUCAUAGUACUGUUGCAGGAAAAUAAAAAAAUGUAUAUUUAAAUAAUUUUAAAGCGACUAUUAGUGUUUCUAACAAAGUUGGUAAUCUAGGACUUUUCUCAGUGUUACUGGUUACUAGUGUUACUAGUGUUUCUUAGUGUUACUGUACAUAAACAAUGUAGAUUGACUUGGUGACUACUCCCAGUUUCCCAUAGACCAUGUAUAUAAAAUAGUAAUUAUAAAGUUAAGGUAUAACACUGUCUAUAUGGCCUCUAGAUGUUUUUGGUUCACUACAGUGGAGCCUCAUUUUAAUGCUAUUGUAUGAAACAACCUAAUUGAUUUUAUGAAGUUUUCAAUAUGUUUUUCUGUUACUUUUUUUUAAUUUGUUUGAGGUUAAAUUGGUCAAAAUGGACCAUUUAUGAGGCUGAGGACACAGAUUAGGCCCUAUGAGUCUGAAGUUUUAUUCCCUUUCAUAAUCACGUAUCAUACUGUCUUUAAAGCCCAGAUCAUUAAUCUUACCAAUAGAUGUCAUUGGUUACAGGGAGAAAUCAGGCAAACGGCUGAGGGUGGGUUGAGGCUAAUCUAUGAUGACUAUGGGGGACUCAACCUUCUGAUGUGUGACAGUAGGGUCACAUUCAGAGAUGAAGGUGAUCAUGUCAGGGGCACUAUUUUUACUAUCUACGUGAUAGCAUGUCACAUCAUAGCUUAGAUCUGUUGAAUUACUCACCAUAAAAUAUGAUGGUAGAUUCUCAUGUUAGGUGAAGCUCAUUAUUUACUUUACUGGAGAAAGGCAAUAUUAAACUUACAAUUUGGACAGCUAAGGUUAGGACAUUGCAUUGUAUAAUAAGCCACCCUAAAACUUGAUGAUUUCUAAUAACAGUAAUCAUUAAUUUGUUUACAAACCUGCAAUUUGGAUAGGAUUUGACUUCGUUUCAUGUGGCAUCAACUGGGAUAGCUCAACUGGGGCUGCAGGAUCCAUUUCUAAGAUGACUCACUUACAUGGCUGGUUCAUAGAAUGGGAUGCCCACUGAUGACAAUGCCAGGCCCUCCAGGGAAACGAGGUAAGAGAGGCCGAAGAGGAGAAUCUGGUCCUCCUGGACAGCCUGGUCCUCAGGGCCCUCCUGGUCCAAAAGGCGAUAAGGGAGAACAAGGUGAUCAGGGACCUAGGAUGGUGUUUCCUAAAAUCAAUCAUGGGUUUCUCUCUGCUGAUCAGCAGCUCAUUAAACGCCGCCUGAUUAAGGGUGACCAAGGACAGGCAGGGCCUCCAGGACCCCCUGGCCCUCCAGGCCCAAGAGGGCCACCUGGGGACACAGGGAAAGAUGGCCCCCGUGGAAUGCCAGGAGUACCCGGUGAACCAGGAAAGCCAGGAGAACAAGGCUUGAUGGGUCCUCUAGGGCCUCCGGGACAAAAGGGUUCUAUUGGAGCACCUGGAAUUCCAGGGAUGAAUGGGCAAAAGGGUGAGCCCGGGUUGCCUGGAGCAGUAGGACAGAAUGGAAUACCAGGACCUAAGGGAGAACCUGGAGAACAAGGUGAAAAGGGAGACGCUGGAGAGAACGGCCCCAAGGGUGACACAGGCGAAAAGGGUGACCCUGGAUCAUCUGCUGCAGGAAUUAAGGGAGAACCUGGGGAAUCUGGUCGUCCAGGGCAAAAGGGUGAACCAGGGCUUCCUGGGCUUCCUGGACUUCCGGGGAUAAAGGGAGAACCAGGUUUCAUUGGUCCUCAAGGAGAACCAGGCUUACCAGGUUUACCAGGAACAAAAGGUGAACGGGGGGAAGCAGGGCCUCCUGGAAGAGGUGAGCGAGGGGAACCUGGAGCCCCCGGACCAAAGGGGAAACAAGGUGAAUCAGGAACUAGAGGCCCAAAGGGGUCAAAGGGGGAUCGUGGAGAAAAAGGGGACUCUGGAGCUCAGGGACCAAGGGGUCCACCUGGUCAAAAAGGGGAUCAAGGAGCCACUGAGAUCAUAGACUACAACGGCAACCUCCACGAAGCCUUACAGAGGAUUACCACCUUAACUGUCACGGGUCCCCCUGGACCUCCUGGACCUCAAGGACUACAAGGGCCAAAGGGAGAGCAGGGAUCUCCAGGAAUCCCAGGAAUGGAUGGAGAGCAGGGACUCAAAGGCUCAAAGGGAGACAUGGGGGACCCAGGUAUGACAGGUGAAAAAGGAGGAAUUGGACUUCCUGGAUUACCGGGAGCCAAUGGAAUGAAAGGAGAAAAAGGAGAUUCUGGAAUGCCGGGUCCACAGGGUCCUUCUAUCAUAGGCCCACCAGGCCCACCAGGUCCCCAUGGCCCACCUGGCCCCAUGGGACCUCAUGGACUUCCUGGACCAAAGGGUGAACCAGGGUUAAAUGGUGUUAAAGGAUUGAAGGGUGAACCAGGUCAAAAGGGUGACAGAGGACCCCUUGGUCUUCCAGGAGCAUCUGGCUUAGACGGAAAGCCAGGAUCCCGGGGUACAGAUGGUCCUAUGGGACCCCAUGGCCCUGCAGGUCCCAAAGGAGAAAGAGGUGAAAAAGGAGCUAUGGGAGAGCCUGGACCAAGAGGGCCCUAUGGGCUGCCUGGGAAAGAUGGAGAGCCUGGUCUUGAUGGCUUCCCUGGUCCACGGGGUGAGAAGGGUGAUCUAGGAGAAAAGGGAGAAAAGGGGGAAAAGGGAAAGAAAGGCAAAAAGGGGCCUAAAGGGGAGAAAGGAGAACAGGGUGCUCCUGGAUUAGAUGCACCCUGCCCGUUGGGGCCAGAUGGCUUACCCAUGCCUGGCUGUUGGCAAAAGUGAUGAAUCUAACCUUUCAAGCAUGAAGUUGUGUAUAUAAGGGUCCAUUUUUAAUAUUUAUAGUUGAAAACUGAAUUGCAGAUUUUACAAGUCUGAGAUAUGUUUACAUAGGGCUGCUUCUUCCUGCUGGCAGUAGUAUACAUGUCCAUUUUUACUCCACUUACAUCUGAAAUUGGGCAAUUUGUGAAACCAGUGAGAAUCCUGCAAAAAAUAUAGAUCAGUAUCUCCUUAUCUUAUGUGAAGAUACGUAUUUAUAUGGACAAAUCAGUGGUAGAGAAUGAUUGAUUGUACUAGCUAUUUUCCUUCUUUUGGCUUGCUAAUUGCAUGGACAAAAAGUGCCAUGAAAUAGUUUACAUGAAAUGGUGACCAAAUAUGGACUCAAAGCUAUGAAAAUGUACUAUACUGACUGAUUUUAGAGCUGAUUAUCACAUUCCCAUUCACCUUUCAUGUCGGCGUUGACUCAUACCUACACCACCCAUUGAAACUAACUAAAAAAGCAUGACUGUGUGCCAAACCUGCUUGCUGUGCAACUUCAGAUGCUAGCAUGUUGAUCAGGAGUCCUUUGAUUACAUCUGAACCUUUAUUCCUUUUGUCAUCUCAAGGGGGUUACACCAUGGCUUAUUGCCAAAAAGAGAUAAGGUGGCGGAGAGCACACACACAAUUUGUCUUGUAUUUUGAGGGAGUUGCAGUCCUGACUGCAGAUCUACAGCUUCCAGUAUUGUGGGCUCAUGUGGCCACUUUGGUUGAAAUACGAAGGGGUUGAGCCUGUUGCUGCCACCAGUUUUCCUUGGGCUGCCCUUGGCAGUGAAGACAUGGGAAGAGGACCGAUUCAGCCUCCAGCACUGCCUCUCAUGUGACCAAGUAGGAAAGAGGUUUACAAAUGCAAACAUGCAGAACCACAGACUUUAAAAAUAUGUAUAAAUAAACUGAAUUUCAGCAAGUGUUAAUAUAGGUGCUUUUAAAAAUGACAGAGGCACAGCACUUCUUUUGGAAUAGGAGAUUCUUGGAAUGGGAGAUCCUGUCCCUGAGGGAAAAGGGAUGUCCAUCCCACCAAAACUUGGGUUGCUGAAGAAAUAACAUGUUCUGAGAAGGGAUCAGCCAAAAUCGCCUCUCCCGAUGAUAUAGGAGAGCUUACUGGGACAAUCUGUGCCAAAGUUGUUGUGAGAGCUUUCCUUCCUCCUACGAUCCAACCAUGUCAAACAUUUCCUACAAAGUUUGAGAAACAGGUAUUUUUCAUUCUUUUUAAUGCUUUUUUCUUUUUCUUUCUUUAGUCCCAAGAAUAUUGAAAAAAUAUUAGUUUCAGUUUUUGUCACAUAUGUUUUGAACAAUUUUUUUAAGAAGUCUUCAAAUCAUAAUAAUUUGGCUCCAGUAGUCAAAAUGACCUUUUACUAACUUCUCUCUUGUUUUGGAUAAUUGGAUAGAAUAUAAAAGAAGCUCCACUUUCAGUCUAAUCAUUGUAAAGCAUGAAAGUUAUGCAUUUUUAAGUAGUUUUGACUUUUUUUACAUGAUGAAUGUAACGUACAUGGAGAUUAUCAGUUAAUAUAAAGCCAAGAUUUUGUCACAUUUGGUAAUAUUAACUAAUUUCUAUUUUUAUGGUUUUAAGUUUUGUCUAUAUUUAGAUUUCUUUCUCUUUUUAACAUUUCUAAAUGUUUGUCUCAUCCUCAUAUCCACAGACCAAAUCUAAGAUCUCAGAAAGCUGUGAAAUAUAGUUGCCAUAAAGAAAAUAUUUUUCAUCUACUUGCUCAAACUUUACCUAACCAUAUUAGAUGGAACAUUUCUUUGCACAGUAAAGAGUUGGUAGCGUGUUUUGAAAUGGCUUAUUCUAAGUGGAAGUGUUACAUUGAAAGAAACAUUAUCAAUGAGGAGUAGGCACCCUUUCAGCCCAUUAGAGAAUUUAAUUUCUCUCCUGACUCAAUGCCAUCUUCUGGGAAGAUUUCUAGUUUCAUGCAUAGGUGUCACCACCAGAAGGGAAAUUAACUCAUCCUUGGCUUAUAGUUAAGAUAUAACCAUAAGACAAGGAACCUAAAAUCCUCAUGAUCUCAUUUAUGUUAUGUAACCAAAUGACAGUCAUACAAAAUGGCAUCUUCUUUUUUUUCUAUUAAAUUUUUAAGGUUGAAAGAUGUUUAAACUAUUAGAUCAGUCUAAUUGGUAACAUUUCUGGUAACAUUCCACACCCCUAAGCCAGUUUAGCAUUUUGAAAAUAAUGGAGGACAUUUUCUAACAAUUUCUUGUAUGGCAUGGUGUUAGGAUAACGUAUUGCUCAAUGUCUGACACAAUUUGUCUUAAAUGGUUUGGAAAAAUGAACUGAAGUGGGUGGAACUACAUUCUCUUCAGGAAAACAAACUACAGUGUCCAGUGGCUAUAUUUUUUUCCCUUCUAUCUUUUUUUCUGCUCCUCUAGUAGAAAGAGGUGGAUUGAAAUGGAUCACUAUUUAAAACUUGCACAGCUUCAGGAGACGAUACCUCAACAUCAAAAGAAAAACACUUUAUGUAUAAAAAAAUUUUUUGAAAUACAGCCCUUCAAAGAAUACUAUUCUGUCCUGUGUGUAUAUUGAGUUUUUGCUCUAUAACUGAUUUGACAACAUCAACUUAUUUCAUGAUUAAAUGAGGUUGUAAACUUUCAUUACAUUUAUUUCCUUGGGAAAAACAAAGGGAUGGAAAUACUCCUCCUUGUUCAGUGGAAUUGCUAGGUCUUAACCAUGAUGGAUAAUCUUUAACUUUUGGUUACUACAAUGUUUUCAAGCAUCCAUUUUGUCAUAUAGAGAAUUCUUAAAUAAUUUCUAAGUGAAUGAAAGAAUUGUGUUUGUUGAUAUGUGUUGAUAGAUAAUAUACUUUCCUUAAAGAUUUCUUUAAUGUGUGUUAUUGGAUAGAGGGUUGAGAAAAUAUACAUGAAAGACACAUUGGAAAUAAGGCAAGGUCAGUUUCUAUUUCUAAUAAAACAUUGAAGGAUAGCAAAUUGAUAUGUGUUUUAGAUUUAAAAUUGUUUUUCAUUUAUGUUGGUUGGUGCUAAUGUAUCUCUUUUCCUUUUUCUCUAUGGACAAUACAACUACUAUGGAUAAUUUUAUUUCCCUGUUUAAUAGCAUUCCUAAAUCAUUAGUGUGUUAUUUUAUUUUUAAAGUUCAUGAAUUUGCUAUAAUUAUGGUCCAAUGACCAGGCUUUCUUAAUGUAAAACAAAACAGUGUACCAAUAGAUGAUGUGUGUUUACUCGGAUCAUGGAUCCUCCUAUUUCAUAUUCAUUUCAUACAUCAUAUGCCUUUAUCUACUUUCAUGUGUCUCAUCUUUUUCAUUCACUCGUCUUUUAGUUUAUAUGAUUUGAUGAAACAUGACAAAACUAGCAUCAGAGAAGUCUGCACACACCGUAUAGAGUACCUAGUGCACAAAUAUACCUAAUUUUUUCUUUCAGUUUUUGUUUUUCAUUAGCAAAAGCAGUCUUGGAGGAUUUUUUUUUCUCAUGUGAUUUUAUAGAGGACAUUAGAAUAUCUUUAAUUCCUACCAGAAGAAAGGUCUUGUUUUUGAAUUUACAUUCUGUGCAUACGAUGUUCUGAUGGGACAGCAAGAACUUACACAUCAACUAGUUUAUACUACAUGUCCUUUGUCUAACUAUCUAUCUAUAUAGACAUAUGUGCUAGUUUAGAAAAUUGUCAAAUCAGCAUGUCAGUACCAAUGGAAAAAUUGUCUUUGAUAUGUUAUAUUUUUCUCACUUAGGAAAUGUGCUUAAUUUCCAAGGGUUUUUUUUUUUAAUGUUACUAUUGAAGCAUGAAAAGUUAACAUCAUUUGUUAUCCUUUCUUUCCCCACUAUAUAUUGUCUUACCCAGAGUAGGGCUAUACUUUGGUGGUGUUUUAACAUCUUCUAAUAAGUGAUCAUAAGCAACAUACAGAUGCUAAUAUUUGAAAUCUUGUUUUUUCUUACUUCCUAAUAAUCAAAUUAUAUUAAUAUUUCACACUACAAAAAAAUAGGAUUUUCUAAUUUGUAAAAACAAGAGCUCCUGCUAUCUCUUGGAAGUUAAGUCCUUAGGAACCCUAUCUUAUCUUUCUAAAAAUAAUAAGUAAGAACAAUCACAUGUGAUUCUGGCUAUUAAAAUCAUACAUCCCUAGUGGAAUUAACAAGCUUGACCAAUUAUGAUUAUGCUAAAUUGUUUUAGGCUAGGAGGACUGUCAGUCCCUACUUCUUCCCAUUUUUCUUGGGAUAUCUUUAUAUUGGCUAGAUUUGUUGCCAAUAUAAAAUUGACACAGCAGAGACACUCCUCUAACUUAAAUUUUUAGUGGAGUUUGGUUUUUGCUAACCCCGUACUAAUAAACACUUUAAUGACUUUUUUCAUUUCAAAAUAUUUAAAUGUAUAAAAUUGCCUAUGCUGCUUAUUGAAAGAACCGUCCUUUUGGGCAUAAGAAGACUUUUUCAACCUAAACCGUUAUGUGUGAUUUAUUAACAACUUAACAAAGAAAGUACCAACAUCUCUCAAAAUGUAGUUGAUAUUCUUACCUAUCUCAGAAAUAUUAACGAAUUGGAUUCACAAAAGAAUGUCUUACAUACUGUUGACAUUUAUGUGAAUAUUCUUUAUACUGUUGUAAAUGUUUCAUUCAACUUAAUAACAUUUUAAAAGAUGUAUGUAUCUGAUUUUUCUUUAGAAAAUAUUAUAUUUUUAUUUGUAUUUUUUACAUUUUAAAGUUCAUCUCUAUGUGCAGCUAUUUUUAUAUUGCCAAAAACUCACAUAAAUACAAAAUAAGUGAAAUAUGCAAAAAAAAAUAUUUUGGCAAGCAUUACACUGCAUAUUUUUUUAAAUGUUUGUGGGCCAGUCUCAUACAAUUGAUUAUUCUAAGAAUGUGUUGUGUCUUAUCACUGUAAAUAUGGCACAAACCUGUUUAUCUCAGUAGUGUAAAUAAUUGAAAGAUUGAAUUCUCCCUGUUCAAUUUUUAUUUUAAUUUCCUUGUAAUUUCUCCAGCUGACAUUACUGUAUCAAAAGAUGCAUAAGAUUUUUGAUUUGCGGUUUGGAGAUAAUUGCAUUGUGUUCAGUUUCCAGUUUGUUUUUAUUUGCUUUUUAAAUUUGUUUUCAGGGUUCCUAGUUUGUGAGAAGUUGAUCUUCAGAAUUAUUUUUACACUAUUUAUGACUUAUUUUCAUAAUGUAAAAAGUGUGUAAUUAUUACAAUAUUAAUCCAAACAAUGAUAAUGAAUUGUAUUGUUAUAAAGCUUUAUUGAUGUUCAUGAAAA